AGAGGCAGUCCUGGGGCUCUGGGGCUCGGGCUUUGUCACCGGGACCCGCAGGAGCCAGAACCACUCGGCGCCGCCUGGUGCAUGGGAGGGGAGCCGGGCCAGGAGUAAGUAACUCAUACGGGCGCCGGGGACCCGGGUCGGGCUGGGGGCUUCCAACUCAGAGGGAGUGUGAUUUGCCUGAUCCUCUUCGGCGUUGUCCUGCUCUGCCGCAUCCAGCCCUGUACCGCCAUCCCACUUCCCGCCGUUCCCAUCUGUGUUCCGGGUGGGAUCGGUCUGGAGGCGGCCGAGGACUUCCCAGGCAGGAGCUCGGGGCGGAGGCCGGGUCCGCGGCAGACCAGGGCAGCGAGGCGCUGGCCGGCAGGGGGCGCUGCGGUGCCAGCCUGAGGCUGGGCUGCUCCGCGAGGAUACAGCGGCCCCUGCCCUGUCCUGUCCUGCCCUGCCCUGUCCUGUCCUGCCCUGCCCUGCCCUGUCCUGUCCUGCCCUGCCCUGCCCUGUGUCCUCAGACAAUAUGUUAGCCGUGCACUUUGACAAGCCGGGAGGACCGGAAAACCUCUACGUGAAGGAGGUGGCCAAGCCGAGCCCGGGGGAGGGUGAAGUCCUCCUGAAGGUGGCGGCCAGCGCCCUGAACCGGGCGGACUUAAUGCAGAGACAAGGCCAGUAUGACCCACCUCCAGGAGCCAGCAACAUUUUGGGACUUGAGGCAUCUGGACAUGUGGCAGAGCUGGGGCCUGGCUGCCAGGGACACUGGAAGAUCGGGGACACAGCCAUGGCUCUGCUCCCCGGUGGGGGCCAGGCUCAGUACGUCACUGUCCCCGAAGGGCUCCUCAUGCCUAUCCCAGAGGGAUUGACCCUGACCCAGGCUGCAGCCAUCCCAGAGGCCUGGCUCACCGCCUUCCAGCUGUUACAUCUUGUGGGAAAUGUUCAGGCUGGAGACUAUGUGCUAAUCCAUGCAGGACUGAGUGGUGUGGGCACAGCUGCUAUCCAACUCACCCGGAUGGCUGGAGCUAUUCCUCUGGUCACAGCUGGCUCCCAGAAGAAGCUUCAAAUGGCAGAAAAGCUUGGAGCAGCUGCUGGAUUCAAUUACAAAAAAGAGGAUUUCUCUGAAGCAACGCUGAAAUUCACCAAAGGUGCUGGAGUUAAUCUUAUUCUAGACUGCAUAGGCGGAUCCUACUGGGAGAAGAACGUCAACUGCCUGGCUCUUGAUGGUCGAUGGGUUCUCUAUGGUCUGAUGGGAGGAGGUGACAUCAAUGGGCCCCUGUUUUCAAAGCUACUUUUUAAGCGAGGAAGUCUGAUCACCAGUUUGCUGAGGUCUAGGGACAAUAAGUACAAGCAAAUGCUGGUGAAUGCUUUCACGGAGCAAAUUCUGCCUCACUUCUCCACGGAGGGCCCCCAACGUCUGCUGCCGGUUCUGGACAGAAUCUACCCAGUGACCGAAAUCCAGGAGGCCCAUAAGUACAUGGAGGCCAACAAGAACAUAGGCAAGAUCGUCCUGGAACUGCCCCAGUGAAGGAGGAUGGGGCAGGACAGGACGCGGCCACCCCAGGCCUUUCCAGAGCAAACCUGGAGAAGAUUCACAAUAGACAGGCCAAGAAACCCGGUGCUUCCUCCAGAGCCGUUUAAAGCUGAUAUGAGGAAAUAAAGAGUGAACUGGAA